CCAGGGAGAUGCAGUUAAAGACUUGAUGCUUCGCUUUCUGGGUGAAAAAGCUGCAGCAAAGAGACAAGUCCUAAAUGCCGACUCAGUGGAACAAUCUUUUGUUGGAUUGAAACAGCUAAUCAGCUGCAGAAACUGGAGGGCAGCAGUGGACCUGUGCGGACGUCUCCUCACAGCCCACGGCCAGGGCUACGGCAAGAGCGGGCUGCUCACCAGCCACACGACAGAUUCACUGCAGCUCUGGUUUGUCAGGCUGGCACUACUAGUGAAGUUGGGCCUUUUCCAGAAUGCUGAGAUGGAAUUUGAACCCUUCGGAAAUCUUGAUCAGCCAGAUCUUUAUUACGAGUACUACCCGCACGUGUACCCUGGGCGCAGGGGCUCCAUGGUCCCCUUCUCGAUGCGCAUCUUGCACGCGGAGCUUCAGCAGUACCUGGGGAACCCACAGGAGUCGCUGGAUAGACUGCACAAGGUGAAGACUGUCUGCAGCAAGAUCCUGGCCAAUUUGGAGCAAGGCUUAGCAGAAGACGGCGGCAUGAGCAGCGUGACUCAGGAGGGCAGACAAGCCUCUAUCCGGCUGUGGAGGUCACGUCUGGGCCGGGUGAUGUACUCCAUGGCAAACUGUCUGCUCCUGAUGAAGGAUUAUGUGCUGGCCGUGGAGGCGUAUCAUUCGGUUAUCAAGUAUUACCCAGAGCAAGAGCCCCAGCUGCUCAGCGGCAUCGGCCGGAUUUCCCUGCAGAUUGGAGACAUAAAAACAGCUGAAAAGUAUUUUCAAGACGUUGAGAAAGUAACACAGAAAUUAGAUGGACUACAGGGUAAAAUCAUGGUUUUGAUGAACAGCGCGUUCCUUCACCUCGGGCAGAAUAACUUUGCAGAAGCCCACAGGUUCUUCACAGAGAUCUUAAGGAUGGAUCCAAGAAACGCAGUGGCCAACAACAACGCUGCCGUGUGUCUGCUCUACCUGGGCAAGCUCAAGGACUCCCUGCGGCAGCUGGAGGCCAUGGUCCAGCAGGACCCCAGGCACUACCUGCACGAGAGCGUGCUCUUCAACCUGACCACCAUGUACGAGCUGGAGUCCUCACGGAGCAUGCAGAAGAAACAGGCCCUGCUGGAGGCUGUCGCCGGCAAGGAGGGGGACAGCUUCAACACACAGUGCCUCAAGCUGGCCUAGCUGCCUCCAACACACUACGUCAGAAGGACCCGGGUCUUUGAAACUGUGUCUUGAAGCUAAUGUAUUAAUGUGACAUGGAGGAACUCAAUAAAACUCCUGCUUCA